GACUCUAAGAACCUGAAGCAGAUUCUCCUCUAGAGAUGAAUUUCCAAACUCUGACAUGGCUCCUGAAAAUUUCACCAGAGUCACUGAGUUUAUUCUUACAGGUGUCUCUAGCUGUCCAGAGCUCCAGAUUCCCCUCUUCCUGGUCUUUCUGGUGCUCUAUGGGCUGACCAUGGCAGGGAACCUGGGCAUCAUCACCCUCACCAGUGUUGACUCUCGACUUCAAACCCCCAUGUACUUUUUCCUGCAACAUCUGGCUCUCAUUAAUCUUGGUAACUCUACUGUCAUUGCCCCUAAAAUGCUGAUUAACUUUUUAGUAAAGAAGAAAACUACCUCAUUCUAUGAAUGUGCCACCCAACUGGGAGGGUUCUUGUUCUUUAUUGUAUCGGAGGUAAUCAUGCUGGCUUUGAUGGCCUAUGACCGCUAUGUGGCUAUUUGUAACCCUCUGCUGUACAUGGUGGUGGUGUCUCGGCGGCUCUGCCUCCUGCUGGUCUCCCUCACAUACCUCUAUGGCUUUUCUACAGCUAUUGUGGUUUCAUCUUAUGUAUUCUCUGUGUCUUAUUGCUCUUCUAAUAUAAUCAAUCAUUUUUACUGUGAUAAUGUUCCUCUGUUAGCAUUAUCUUGCUCUGAUACUUACUUACCAGAAACAGUUGUCUUUAUAUCUGCAGCAACAAAUGUGGUUGGUUCCUUGAUUAUAGUUCUAGUAUCUUAUUUCAAUAUUGUUUUGUCUAUUUUAAAAAUAUGUUCAUCAGAAGGAAGGAAAAAAGCCUUUUCUACCUGUGCUUCACAUAUGAUGGCAGUCACAAUUUUUUAUGGGACAUUGCUAUUCAUGUAUGUGCAGCCCCGAAGUAACCAUUCACUGGAUACUGAUGAUAAGAUGGCUUCUGUGUUUUACACGUUGGUAAUUCCUAUGCUGAAUCCCUUGAUCUACAGCCUGAGGAAUAAGGAUGUGAAGACUGCUCUACAGAGAUUCAUGACAAAUCUGUGCUAUUCCUUUAAAACAAUGUAAUUUUAAACAGUACAGGUAAAUGAGGAGAGAGUUAAUAUAAGCUGCCAUUAUGUAAAAGAAAAUGUAGGAAAAAGAAAAGGUAGGUAGCCGAGUUACAGGUUCGUAAGCAAUCAUAAGAAUUACAACAAGAUACAAUUUAGGGAGCUUUGAAUUAAAAAAUAAACUGAAACCCUUUGAGUUGUGAGGUUAAGUUAGAAAAAAAAAAUGUUAUUUACCAAUUCUGCCUGGGAUUAAGCAGGUAGACAGUUUGAAAUAAAAAUGGUUUCCAGCAGUUAGAAAAAAAAAUUAAAAAAAGUUAAAUAAGUUUGAAUGAG